GUUAGUGGGCUUGGGCGUUGGGUGAAGUAUCCAGGUUGGGCGCUUCCAGCGCUUUCUGUGGCGGGGGAAUGAAGGCCUAGGUCAGGGAAUAGGAAGGUGUAUCGCCGCCAGAGUGCGGAACACCCUCGCCUUGAGGGUUCCCACAGUGACUUGCAAAAGUCUAGUGAGACCCGAGAAUGCUGAGGCGGGACACGAAGCAUGUGGUUCUUGUGGUUGCGACGCUCGUGCCGCCAUCUUGGGUGCUGGCGGCGGAAACCGGUACCCCAACUUCCCCUCGGUGCGAACCUGGAGAAGCCACCCCAGCUGUGAGGGACGGUUGCGCCUCAUGGCCCAGGCAAGGGUACCUUCGCUGGAGCAGUACCGCGGACGGAUAUCAUGAGGGUGGUGGGACGUUGGCGGAACGUUGGCGGAACGUUGGCGGUGUGAGAGGUGUGGGGUAAUGGCGAUUUUUGUCAUGGUAGAAACAGCCCAAAGGACCCCCCUCGUUUGGCCUCCCACGCAGCUUAGUCUUGCUUUUUUAGGGAUGUUUCUCAUUUUUUAAUUUCUCCAGUCCCAUCUGGUUAUAUUGCCAAAACAUGUUUGUGACUCUCAAACGUUAGUUUACUCCCAGCAUCACUUGGGGAGCUUGCUAAGCUACGAAUUCCGAGGUCCCACUGGAGAGUCUGAUUUAAUGACCCUGGAGUGGCGGCCGGAUAACCUGCCUGCUGGGGUGAUUUUAACGCAGCUGAUGCGAAGACCCCAUUUAGGGAAUCAUUGGGUUGGCGUUUGCAAUGCGUUCCUCCCAGCUAUAGGACAAAGAGGUGUCAACUCAACUGUGUCUUCUUAGAAGAGCCCAUUAUUUAUAGUAUUAUGAUGACACAUUCCCCUCCAUGAAGGAGCAGAUGGUUUUCGAGAAAAAUGUCUUCAACAAGACCAGCCGGACUGAGAGUGAGAUUGCAUUUUUUGGGGGUAUGACCAUCGUCUACAAGAACAGCAUUGACCUCUUCCUAUACGUGGUGGGCUCAUCCUACGAGAAUGAGCUGAUGCUCAUGUCUGUUCUCACCUGCCUGUUUGAGUCUCUGAACCACAUGUUAAGGAAGAACGUGGAGAAGCGCUGGUUGCUGGAGAACAUGGACGGAGCCUUCUUGGUGCUGGACGAGAUUGUGGAUGGCGGUGUGAUUCUGGAGAGUGACCCCCAGCAAGUGAUCCAGAAGGUGAAUUUUAGGGCAGAUGAUGGCGGCUUGACUGAACAGAGUGUGGCCCAGGUCUCUCUGCUCAGACUAAUCCUGCUUGUAUGGAACUUCCCGCCCUGGCGCUAACUCCUCGUGCUGUGGUGGCCCUACCGAGAUGAGCCUGUGCUGUCUCGUGUGGAGUCCCAG